AUGUGGCGCGCGCCGGAAGCGGCUCUGAGGCCGGAAGUGAGCCUAGAGCGCCGCGGCCCCGAGAUGAAGCCGGCGGUGGACGAGAUGUUCCCCGAGGGCGCCGGGCCCUACGUGGACCUGGACGAGGUGGCACGGGCCCGGCGGGAGUCUCCGAGCGCGGGAGGCAGCACCGGGCUCUUGAUGGACUUGGCAGCCAAUGAAAAGGCCGUUCAUGCAGACUUUUUUAACGAUUUUGAAGAUCUUUUUGAUGAUGAUGACAUCCACAGCUCAGGACUGCCCAGGACAAGCCAGCAGUCCUCCAUGGUUCCCGCACUGCAGCGAGGGCAGUCGGAGCACGGGGUCCGUGGGAAGGCAGCAGAGCGGCCUGUGGUGUCGGAAGAGAGAUGUGAACUGAACGGGAGAGAAGUGGCAGCUUUGGACAGAGCGUUUGGGAGCACAGGCCAUGGGCAGGGGGCGGAGGCGCUAAUGUUUACCAGAUGCAGAGAACAUCCGCUGUGUGGCACCAACAAAGCAACAAGUGAGGGGAAAAUGGGCACAGGACGCUUAAGAAACAGUUUACGGAAGAACCAAUCCAAGUGGCUGGGAAGUUAUCUAGAGGUGCUCAGAACCACAAGAAGCAGGCGAGAGGUCAGCGAAGACAGCACAAUAUCAGUUUCUACUCACUGGAGGGGUAAAUGUUUUAAGAGUGAUGAAACACCAUCCGUUGCUGGUGGAGAAGAAGGGAAGAAGACCACACAGCCAUGCAUAGAUGUGAGGUAG